AGUCCUUCACUGAGGAGCCAGAGGGAAUCAAUUCCACAAGCUGGGUUGAGGAGAACAGGAGAUGGAGAAAGCAAGUGGAAGACAGUCCAUUGCUCUGUCCACAGUGGAGACUGGCACAGUGAACCCGGGGCUGGAGCUCAUGGAAAAAGAAGUAGAGCCUGAGGGAAGCAAGAGGACUGACGCACAAGGACACAGCCUGGGGGAUGGACUGGGCCCUUCCACUUACCAGAGGAGGAGUCGGUGGCCUUUCAGCAAAGCAAGAAGUUUCUGCAAAACACACGCCAGCUUGUUCAAGAAGAUCCUGUUGGGCCUGUUGUGUUUGGCCUAUGCUGCCUAUCUCCUGGCAGCUUGCAUCUUGAAUUUCCAGAGGGCACUGGCCUUGUUUGUCAUCACCUGCUUGGUGAUCUUUGUCCUGGUUCACUCGUUUUUGAAAAAGCUCCUGGGCAAAAAAUUAACAAGAUGUCUGAAGCCCUUUGAAAACUCCCGCCUGAGGCUUUGGACGAAAUGGGUGUUUGCAGGAGUCUCCUUGGUUGGCCUUAUACUGUGGUUGGCUUUAGACACAGCCCAAAGGCCAGAGCAGCUGAUCCCCUUUGCAGGAAUCUGCAUGUUCAUCCUUAUCCUCUUUGCCUGCUCCAAACACCACAGCGCAGUGUCCUGGAGGACAGUGUUUUCGGGCCUAGGUCUUCAAUUUGUCUUUGGGAUCUUGGUCAUCAGAACUGAUCUUGGAUAUACUGUAUUUCAGUGGCUGGGAGAGCAGGUCCAGAUUUUCCUGAACUACACUGUGGCCGGCUCCAGUUUUGUCUUUGGGGAUACACUGGUCAAGGAUGUCUUUGCUUUUCAGGCCUUACCAAUCAUCAUUUUCUUUGGAUGUGUGGUGUCCAUUCUCUACUACCUGGGCCUUGUGCAAUGGGUAGUUCAGAAGGUCGCCUGGUUUUUACAAAUCACUAUGGGCACCACUGCUACAGAGACCCUGGCUGUGGCAGGAAACAUCUUUGUGGGUAUGACAGAGGCACCUCUGCUCAUCCGUCCCUACCUUGGGGACAUGACACUCUCUGAAAUCCAUGCGGUGAUGACUGGAGGGUUUGCCACCAUUUCUGGCACUGUGCUGGGAGCCUUCAUAGCCUUUGGGGUUGAUGCAUCAUCCCUGAUUUCUGCCUCUGUGAUGGCCGCCCCUUGUGCUCUCGCCUCAUCAAAGCUAGCGUAUCCGGAAGUGGAGGAGUCCAAGUUCAAGAGUGAGGAGGGGGUAAAGCUGCCCCGUGGGAAGGAGAGGAAUGUCCUGGAAGCUGCCAGCAACGGAGCCGUAGAUGCCAUAGGCCUUGCUACUAAUGUAGCAGCCAACCUGAUUGCCUUUUUGGCUGUGUUGGCCUUCAUCAAUGCUGCCCUCUCCUGGCUGGGGGAAUUGGUGGACAUACAGGGGCUCACUUUCCAGGUCAUCUGCUCCUAUCUCCUAAGGCCCAUGGUUUUCAUGAUGGGUGUAGAGUGGACAGACUGUCCAAUGGUGGCUGAGAUGGUGGGAAUCAAGUUCUUCAUAAAUGAGUUUGUGGCUUAUCAGCAACUGUCUCAAUACAAGAACAAACGUCUCUCUGGAAUGGAGGAGUGGAUUGAGGGAGAGAAACAGUGGAUUUCUGUGAGAGCUGAAAUCAUUACAACAUUUUCACUCUGUGGAUUUGCCAAUCUUAGUUCCAUAGGAAUCACACUUGGAGGCUUGACAUCAAUAGUACCUCACCGGAAGAGUGACUUGUCCAAGGUUGUGGUCAGGGCCCUCUUCACAGGGGCCUGUGUAUCCCUUAUCAGUGCCUGUAUGGCAGGAAUCCUCUAUGUCCCCAGGGGAGCUGAAGCUGACUGUGUCUCCUUCCCAAACACAAGUUUCACCAAUAGAACCUAUGAGACCUACAUGUGCUGCAGAGGGCUCUUUCAGAGUACUUCUCUGAAUGGCACCAACCCUCCUUCUUUUUCUGGUCCCUGGGAAGAUAAGGAGUUCAGUGCUAUGGCCCUUACUAACUGCUGUGGAUUCUACAACAAUACCGUCUGUGCCUAAGGCUGCUUGAUCUAUUUCUAUAACAGUUUUGAUCUUAAAAGCUUUGUGAUUGCAAAGGUGUUUAUGUACUCAGGGUGCCCACAACUCACUCACCAAGAUGUUUAACAGUAAGUAACAGUAAAUGUAAAAGAUUCAUUUUGGGCCGGGCUCAGUGGCUCAUGCCUGUAAUCCCAGCACUUUGGGAGGCCGAGGCGGGCGGAUCACAAGGUCAGGAGAUCGAGACCAUCCUGGCUAACACAGUGAAACCCCGUCUCUACUAAAAAUACAAAAAAUUAGCCGGGAGUGGUGUCGGGCGACUGUAGUCCCAGCUACUCGCGAGGCUGAGGCAGGAGAAUGGCGUGAAUCCGGGAGGCGGAGCUUGCAGCGAGCCAAGAUCGCGCCACUGCACUCCAGCCUGGGUGACAGAGCGAGACUCUGUCUCAAAAAAAAAAAAAAAAAAAAAGAUUCAUUUUGGUUCGCUGUAUCCCAAUAACGAAAAAUAGCUUUUGUUUUUCCAUUAUUUGGCUGAACCAAAAAAUGGCAUUCCUCAUGGGCCCUGCCUGAACUUUCAUUUGAAAAAAUAAGUAUUACUGUCCAACAAUGAUAGACUGGAUUAAGAAAAUGUGGCACAUAUACACCAUGGAAUACUAUGCAGCCAUAAAAAAUGAUGAGCUCAUGUCCUUUGCAGGGACAUGGAUGAAAUUGGAAAUCAUCAUUCUCAGUAAACUAUCGCAAGGACAAAAAACCAAACACCACAUGUUCUCACUCAUAGAUGGGAAUUGAACAAUGAGAACACAUGGACACAGGAAGGGGAACAUCACACUCUGGGGACUGUUGUGGGGUGAGGGGAAGGGGGAGGGAUAGCAUUAGGAGAUAUACCUAAUGCUAAAUGACGAGUUAAUGGGUGCAGCACACUAGCAUGGCACAUGUAUACAUAUGUAACUAACCUGCAUAUUGUGCACAUGUACCCUAAAACUUAAAGUAUAAUAAUAAUAAUAAAAGAAAAAACUUCAUAAAAUAAAGUGAAGCACCCACCAAAAAAUAAAAUAAAUAAAAUAAAUAAAUAAAAGAAAAAAUAAGUAUUACUAUGUCAAAAAAGUCUUACAAAUCAUGCUUCUAGUUGCCAUCUUAAAAAUUAUGUGAUGCAGUGUGCUAUAAAUGUGAUUUAGUAUGUAAUUUGCCUGGGACGGGGGAGAAGCUACAUUUAUUGGCAUUGUGGAUGAGCUGGAUUUAUAUUACUGAUGUUACCUUUGAAAGGUAUAUGAAUAUUUAAUGAUAAGAUUUUUCUGGUUGUCAAACAUUUGUAAAUCUGCAAACUUCUUAACAACAUUACACAGUAAACAAAAAAUACUUCCUGUAUACUAAGGAAGACUUCUAAGGAAUAUCCAUUUCUUAAAGGCCAUUACUUUGUUGUAGUAUUCUGCUUUAGUGCUAGCCACAUUUGCUCCAAGUUUAUGGGGAAGCCUUUAAAACAGUAAUUUUCAGUGGGAAGGGGCCAAUUUUGCUUUUCAGAGGACAUCUGACAGUGUGUCUCCAGACAUUAUUGGUGAUUAAAGUGGGAGGAUGCUACUGACAUCUAGUGAGUAGAGGCCAAUAUUGCUACUAAAAUUCCUAUAACCAAAGGUCAGCUCUCCCACAACGAAGAAUUACCUGGUCCCAAACGUCAAUUGUGCUGAGACUCAGAAACUCUGAUUCAAAAUAUUUUAGAUAUUUAUUAUAUUUAAUAUUAUUUAUUAUAUUAAUAUUAUAGCCUUAAGGAAGGGUUUCAAAAGGAUACAGGAGUUCCUCAAAAAGUUAAACACAGAAUUACCAUAGAGCCCCACAAUUCCACUCCUACAUACACAUUCAAAAGAAUCAAAACUAAGUUCUCAAACAAGUACAUGUACAUGCAUGUUCACAGUAGCACUAUUCAAAAUAGCCAAAAAUUGGAAACAGUCUAAAUGUCCAUCAAUGGAUAAAUUGUGUUACAUACACACAAUGGAAUUUUAUUCACCCAUUAAAAAAAGAAGUACUGAUUUAUGCUAUGUAGAGGCACCCCGAAAACAUGCUAAACGAAAGAAGCUAGACACAAAAGUCUUAUUAUUGCAUGAUUCCAUUUAGAUGAAAUAUUCAGAAUAUAUAAAUCCAUAGAGACAGAAGGGAGAUGGUGGUUGCCAGGGCCUGGGGAAGGAGGGAUUAGAGAGUGACUCCUUAACGAGUUUGGGGUUUUCCUUUGGGGUGAUGGGAAUGUUUUGGAACGAGAUAGAGGUGGUGGUUGUGCAACAUUGUGAAUAUUAUGUCACUGAAUUGUUCACUUUAAAAUGGCUGUUUAUGUUAUGUGAAUUUCACCUCAAUAAAAAAAAUUUUUAGAAGGA